UUUUUAACUUUUAGGCUCUGGAGUGCAUGUGCAGGUUUGUUAUAUAGGUAAACUGCAUGUCACAGGGGUUUAGUGUACUGAUUAUUUGCCACCCAGCUAAUAAGUAUAGUACACCAUAGGUAGUUUUUCAAUCCUCUCUCUCCUCUCACGACCGUCAAGUACACAUGUAGGAGCAAGAGAUUUUUAGUAAGAAGAGAGGAAUAAUGGUUUGAAAGGAAUCAAAAGGAGCAAAGAGAACCUAUACACCACAUUCCCACACUGAAGUACUUAGAGUUUCAGAGAAUAAGUAGAGUCUCUACCUGAAAUACACAGGAAGCAAUGUCCUCAAGGGAAAUCCAAAUUACAUUUAAAGCCAGGAGAAGCAAGGAACUGUCCGUAAAGAAGCAGUCUAAGGAAAUAGGGAAGUUUACUAAUCAUGCAGCUGAACUUCCAUAGAGUACAACUGAAAGUAAGGGAGGAAAAGGGUGUUGGGUCAAGAAAGAACAAUCAGAAUAUUAUGGUGAUAAAAAUACCAGAGAGAAUAGGUGAGCAAAGGGACUUAUGAUUUGGAUGGUGAUCAAAGAAACCAGGAAUGGUCAGCAGAGGGGGUUGCUUCAUCAGACUAAAGAAAGGGGGAGGGUGCACUCUCCUUAGUUAUCUGACAUGGAGACAGGCAUCUCUGGUAGUGAGCAAGGAAGUCCAAAUCUAGUCGUUAGGCACCCAGGAGUGGGCAGUCAUCCUGCCAGUCUCAGCCCUACGUUUAUGGUUCCAGUUAAGAGUAAGUCAUCAAACCAAGAGAACACAGGAACCAAGAUGGUACGCUCCAAAAAGUUCAGUUCUGCUCUGAAGCGCCCCCUACAGGAUCCUGUUCAGAGACGCAGGAGGAGGCAAAGCUGCUGGUCUGCGCUUUGCGCCAUUCUGUGCUCCCUCCUACCUGCCCUCUUUUGGCCCAAGUUCUAGUCCCAUCUGCUUUGUCACCCCCUGCCCACCUAAGGGACUUCAUUCUCUGGUCUUCACCGUCCUCAUGGUAAAAUGGACGUGACAUCUUUAAUCACACAUAUCUAUCCAGUGAUGUAAAUGCAGUGAAAAGGGCUUUGAACAGUGUUGUCAGGGAAGGAGACUGAGGCACUAAUUUCUUCCCAUUUUCCCAAUUCCUGCUUCAGCACCGCUCACCUAGGCUCCAGCCCUCUAAAUCUAUCCUAGCCCUUUGGUCGAUCUUUGCCUACUGAGGGCAAAAUUACAUAGUAUCCCAAAAACAAGGAUUAAUACUACAGCCCCAUUUCUUCUCUUUGCCAUUUCCCAUGACAACUCUUAAACCUAGAAACUGGUGCCAUUUCCCUGAUUGGUGGGACCUGCUCACUAGACCAAAAGGGAUGUGUAUGUACAUUUCAUAAUGGGCAUUCAGUUAGGGGAUGAUGUGAGGGCUGUGUGUGAGAUAAAUCCUGGAGUUGGUCUGGCCACAUCCCAAUGACUCAUUUGGACUCCUUUGGACAAGUAACUAGAGCUCCCAUUUGAAAGAAUGACAAGCAAGCUACCUCAAAUUUCUCUUUCUCAACCCAUGACUUCACCUUUUCUGUUCCUUAAUGCUCUCAUCAUCCAGCCCUCCUUUCUGCUGUUUUUCCUCAGUUUUCAAGCCUGCACCCUAGUCUUCUGUGCCAUCCCACUUUUUUGGGGUUCUGCCCUAUCUGUUACCCCUCUCCGAAUAAUGUCAGCCCCGCCCACUACCCUACUGUAAGGAUCUGCCCAGCUCUUCCUCUGUGGGUUUUAAACCGUGCAUCUGCUGCCACCACGUUCAUCAGGGUCCCAAUUUCCAUUACACCCCUGCCUUUCCCCCGCUCCUCCUCCUAGCCCUUGUUUCUAAUCCCCUGUACUCUAGCUCCCACUCCCAAUCGAGCCACCCCCAACCAACCAUGACAAUUCACAGCUCUCAUCCUGGAGAGAUGGUUUCCCUCAUGCUGGGACAGUUCUGGGGCAGUUCAGAAUUGCCAGGACUGUGGAUUCCCAGCAGCUUGGCCUGGUGGACACACGGAAUGCAAGACAACAGCAAACCCACCUUCAGCCUUGGUAAGUGACAGGACCCCUUUUCCAUGACCAGAUCCUGGUUACCUUGAUACUAUUUCUAUUUUGUCUCCAUUCCCGUCUGGGCAAUCCUCUUCAGAUGCCAGAGAUUUCCUUUUUUUUGACAGUUUGCUCCUUUCCUCUCAUGCCUGGUCAGCCAGCCUGCAUGAGGUUCUCUACGUUUGAGACUGGCUUCUCCACGGAACUUGGUCUGUAGCCACAGAGCAAACUGCAGGGCCAUUGACAGAGAAUGAAGAGGAGAGUGAAGAGUGGAACACAUCUAAUGUGUUCUCUGGAGGUUCAUACAGUCACCAGGAAGCCCAUGUCUUGGCAUGAUAACCUGGAGGAACCUGCAGAUGCCAGGUUUCUGAAUCUCAUUCACCAUGCUGCCCAGGGACCAAGGAAGAAGUACCCAGAGACACAGACUGAAAACCAGGAAGUUGGAUGGGACUUAGAGCCCUUGGUAAGCGUGGCUCCUUCCUCAGGAAAUACGAGGAAACACAGCAGCAAUAUCAACCCAGAACGCCAUGACCGCAGGCUGAAUCACUUCAGGGUCUGCAGUGACAUCACUCUGUACAAGGCUAAAACGUGGGGCUUAGGAGAUGAUCACCACAAGUAGCAUCCCAGCGGAUGAGCCCAUCUGUGGAUCUAAUGCCUUAAGUGUGCACAGCCCAGAGAAAUAAAAUACUACUUUAAAACGAA